CCCCCACUGGCUGCUCUGAAAAGCCAUCUUUGCAUUGUUCCUCAUCCGCCUCCUUGCUCGCCGCAGCCGCCUCCGCCGCGCGCCUCCUCCGCCGCCGCGGACUCCGGCAGCUUUAUCGCCAGAGUCCCUGAACUCUCGCUUUCUUUUUAAUCCCCUGCAUCGGAUCACCGGCGUGCCCCACCAUGUCAGACGCAGCCGUAGACACCAGCUCCGAAAUCACCACCAAGGACUUAAAGGAGAAGAAGGAAGUUGUGGAAGAGGCAGAAAAUGGAAGAGACGCCCCUGCUAACGGGAAUGCUGAGAAUGAGGAAAAUGGGGAGCAGGAGGCUGACAAUGAGGUAGACGAAGAAGAGGAAGAAGGUGGGGAGGAAGAGGAGGAGGAAGAAGAAGGUGAUGGUGAGGAAGAGGAUGGAGAUGAAGAUGAGGAAGCUGAGUCAGCUACGGGCAAGCGGGCAGCUGAAGAUGAUGAGGAUGACGAUGUCGAUACCAAGAAGCAGAAGACCGACGAGGAUGACUAGACAGCAAAAAAGGAAAAGUUAAACUAAAAAAAAAAAGGCCGCCGUGACCUAUUCACCCUCCACUUCCCGUCUCAGAAUCUAAACGUGGUCACCUUCGAGUAGAGAGGCCCGCCCGCCCACCGUGGGCAGUGCCACCCGCAGAUGACACGCGCUCUCCACCACCCAACCCAAACCAUGAGAAUUUGCAACAGGGGAGGAAAAAAGAACCAAAACUUCCAAGGCCCUGCUUUUUUUCUUAAAAGUACUUUAAAAAGGAAAUUUGUUUGUAUUUUUUAUUUACAUUUUAUAUUUUUGUACAUAUUGUUAGGGUCAGCCAUUUUUAAUGAUCUCGGAUGACCAAACCAGCCUUCGGAGCGUUCUCUGUCCUACUUCUGACUUUACUUGUGGUGUGACCAUGUUCAUUAUAAUCUCAAAGGAGAAAAAAAACCUUGUAAAAAAAGCAAAAAUGACAACAGAAAAACAAUCUUAUUCCGAGCAUUCCAGUAACUUUUUUGUGUAUGUACUUAGCUGUACUAUAAGUAGUUGGUUUGUAUGAGAUGGUUAAAAAGGCCAAAGAUAAAAGGUUUCUUUUUUUUUCCUUUUUUGUCUAUGAAGUUGCUGUUUAUUUUUUUUGGCCUGUUUGAUGUAUGUGUGAAACAAUGUUGUCCAACAAUAAACAGGAAUUUUAUUUUGCUGAGUUGUUCUAACAAAGCUGUCUCAA